AGACAGCGCAAGCCCCACGCCACGCGUCGCUGGUCCCAGGCAGCGAGUCGCUCGCGCGCCCCGCCGCCCGCCUGGCGACAGCUCCGCCGCGCACGCACAUGGAGGGGAGCGCGAGCCCCCCGGAAAAGCCCCGCGCCCGCCCUGCGGCUGCCGUGCUGUGCCGGGGCCCGGUAGAGCCGCUGGUCUUCCUGGCCAACUUUGCCUUGGUCCUGCAGGGCCCGCUCACCACGCAGUAUCUGUGGCACCGCUUCAGCGCCGACCUCGGCUACAAUGGCACCCGCCAAAGGGGGGGCUGCAGCAACCGCAGCGCGGACCCCACCAUGCAGGAAGUGGAGACCCUUACCUCCCACUGGACCCUCUACAUGAACGUGGGCGGCUUCCUGGUGGGGCUCUUCUCGUCCACCCUGCUGGGAGCUUGGAGCGACAGUGUGGGCCGCCGCCCGCUGCUAGUGCUGGCCUCGCUGGGCCUGCUGCUCCAGGCCCUAGUGUCCGUUUUUGUGGUGCAGCUGCAGCUCCACGUCGGCUACUUCGUGCUGGGUCGCAUCCUUUGUGCCCUCCUCGGCGACUUCGGUGGCCUUCUGGCUGCUAGCUUUGCGUCCGUGGCAGAUGUCAGCUCCAGUCGCAGCCGCACCUUCCGGAUGGCCCUGCUGGAAGCCAGCAUCGGGGUGGCUGGGAUGCUGGCAAGCCUCCUCGGGGGCCACUGGCUCCGGGCCCAGGGUUAUGCCAACCCCUUCUGGCUGGCCUUGGCCUUGCUGAUAGCCAUGACUCUCUAUGCAGCUUUCUGCUUUGGUGAGACCUUAAAGGAGCCAAAGUCCACCCGGCUCUUCACGUUCCGUCACCACCGAUCCAUUGUCCAGCUCUAUGUGGCUCCCGCCCCAGAGAAGUCCAGGAAACAUUUAGCCCUCUACUCACUGGCCAUCUUCGUGGUGAUCACUGUGCACUUUGGGGCCCAGGACAUCUUAACCCUUUAUGAACUAAGCACACCCCUCUGCUGGGACUCCAAACUAAUCGGCUAUGGUUCUGCAGCUCAGCAUCUCCCCUACCUCACCAGCCUGCUGGCCCUGAAGCUCCUGCAGUACUGCCUGGCCGAUGCCUGGGUAGCUGAGAUCGGCCUGGCCUUCAACAUCCUGGGGAUGGUGGUCUUUGCCUUUGCCACUAUCACGCCUCUCAUGUUCACAGGAUAUGGGUUGCUUUUCCUGUCAUUAGUCAUCACACCUGUCAUCCGGGCUAAACUCUCCAAGCUGGUGAGAGAGACAGAGCAGGGUGCUCUCUUUUCUGCUGUGGCCUGUGUGAAUAGCCUGGCCAUGCUGACGGCCUCCGGCAUCUUCAACUCACUCUACCCAGCCACUCUGAACUUUAUGAAGGGGUUCCCCUUCCUCCUGGGAGCUGGCCUCCUGCUCAUCCCGGCUGUUCUGAUUGGGAUGCUGGAAAAGGCUGAUCCUCACCUCGAGUUCCAGCAGUUUCCCCAGAGCCCCUGAUCUGCCUGGACCAGAAGACAGAGGGCAAGAGGAGCAAAGUGAACACCAAGCAACUGGAGGUCUGCAGCUGGAAGCCCAGCCCACAGCAGGACAAGCAACUCUUGUCUAAGGGCAGUGCUCUCUUUGGACGAGGUAGUCAAGAGAGACCAAGGCACCACCCCAUCCACAGCUGACCCAGCCUCUGUCUAGGAUCUAGAAUCAUAACCCACACAGGCCCACUGCAGGACAGGUGGCAGAGGAGCUAUUUGGGACAGGAGUCAGUUCUCCCUUUCUGCUAUCCAUCACUUAUAACCCCACAGGCCAGAGGAGAGGUCCUGAGAGAGGUGACACUUCAGGGACCAGAGGCAGCACGAGGGCUGGCAUCUCUCCUUCCAGCCCAAACUGCACAGCCCCAACCAGGUUCCCAACACGUGUAGCAGUCAUCAGCCAUUCCUUAACAAUGAAUGUGGUACCUGGUUAGUGCCAGCCUUGGGAAGGAGGGAGGGAGGUAAGAGGGGCUUGGUGAUCUCUGGAGGAAGAGUGUUGCCUUUGCUGUGGUUGGGGAAUCGAUCCUUGGCUAUGGCCUACCCACUCCCCUGGCUGAAGAGUGCCAAUCAUUACAAAUCAGCUUCAGCAAACUGAAACAAACCUUCUGGUGCCUUGGGCUUUGGGGCCCUCUGUUUUCCUGCUCCCAGUCUGCCUGCCAUACGUUAGACAACAGAAGCUGCUGGGCUGGGCAGGAGCCCUGAGCUGCCUGGUGGAUUGGUACCAAGUGGGGCCAGCCAGGGCUUCUACUGACUCGCUGUGCAACCUUGAGCAAGCCCCACUAGGAACGGCUAGAUCAGCAAUGCCCCAAAUUGUUGAAUCGUGGUGAUCACAUUUGGAUGGACAAGUUAGGAAACUUAGCUGAUUCUCUGAGAUACUUCCCACUUCCUCAUACAUUCUACAAUGAGAUGCCUCUCUUCAUGGGCCUGGGGAAAGGAUGAAUGAGUGUGGCUGGACUUUUGACCUUUAAUGUCCCUGAGCAGUUCUUGGCCCUUGGGGAGAAGUAGGGGGAGGAUCUGGCUGACUCAGCCCCAACCGAGGGGUAGCAGCUGCAGCCCAGCCAAGCAGAACACCCUGGCCCUACAGACCUGUGUCUGAGCAGGCUUUGGAGGAAAGGCCACUUCUGAGUCCUCUGUCUCAGGAGAAGCCAGGCCUAGGUGCUUGACCUGGUGAUCUGAGCUGUGUUUGUCCUAGUAUGGGUGGCAGUCACCUCUGAACACACUGGCCUUGGCUUAGAGGAGGCUUGUGACUUCAGCUGUUCCAGCUGGGGCUGGAUGCUGGACUCUGAUUCCCUCAGAGAGACAGAAGAUCGGGCAGAGGUCAACCAGAAGGCCACACAGGGCAGUGGACAACAGUGGAGGGUAUACCAAAUAGAAAUAAAACGCAGGAAACCUCUCUGAAUACUGCCCUUGGGGACCUCAGGAGGGAGUGGGACUGAUUGGAGACAAAGAGCCAGAAAUCAUCCCCUGGAGAUACUCAGACACUGUAUUGUUAUUGGCGCUGUCCUGUGAGGGCAGUGUCCAGGCUGCCCUGCUUGUCAUAUCCAUGCCCUGGCUCUGGCCCCGGUGAGCACUUGUGCUGCAUGAGGAAAGGAGGAUCAGGUGGGGUCAAAACCAAAGCAUCGAGGCUGGCACUGGCCAAGACAGACUCUGGCAGGGAGGGGAGUGGAAGGAAGGAGCCCCAAACCUGGAGUGAGACCUUUGACUUUCUGAUGAUGUGGCCAAGAACUAGGAGUCACCUGGCCAGCACAGCCAAGAGUGGGGCUGGGGGCGCAGCCAGCUUUAAGGUGUCAACACCUGGCCCUUGCGGGGAAAGAGCCUUCAGCAGCCCCCACGGCCUGGAGCCUGGGUUUAUUGGAGGGUGCUUUCUUACCCUCUGAACCCAGUGGAGGAGGGGGCAAUGGGAUAUUCCUGCUCUGUAUGGCCUCUGGGUCAGCUUUUUGUUGCAAAAUCCUAUCCCCCGCUGCUAGAUUCUUUGAAGCAAGGGAGAAGCAAUAGCCCAGCCUCAGAAUGAUUCUCAGGAAAGCAAUUCCACUGCCAGUGGACUGGGUGCCAGGAGGCCUAGGUCUGGAUCUGGGGCUGCCACUAAUGACAGGAAAGUGGGCUUAUCCUCAACCUUUCUGAGCCUCAGUGUCAUUAUCUGUAAAAUGGGGAUGAUAAUACCAGGUAGAGUUGCUCUGAUGACUGGAGACCAUGGAGCGGAGUGUUUGGGAAAUGGCAAAGAUUUGUGAGGGCUUCGUGCUUUAGAGAUUUGCUACCCUUAACCACCAGCAUCAGCUCACCUGGGAAUCUGUAAGAAAUGCAGAGUCCUAGGCCCCACCCCAGAUCUCCUGAUUUUAACAACAUUCCCAGGUGACUUGGAUGCAUGUUAAAGUUGGAGAAGCUGCCCUAAGUGACAACCCUUUGCCUUUUCAGGACUUUGCCUCUUUCCACAGAGCUGCAGGUUCUGUCUAGGCUGCUUUUACUGCCAUGGGGGCUGCCUGGUCCCUGAGUAAGCAGUGGGUAGCCCUGGAUGGCUGAGGGGCUGGGGAAGCCAGCUGGGCCAGACCAGGAAGGAGCCUGAGGCACAGCACCAAGGCAUGGGGUAGGGUGGGCUUUGAGGCACGGCCUCCCCAUGCCCAGACCCAGGCCCAAACAGGAGGCUCCUGUGCACCAGCAAGUGCAGCAAAGCUGGCUGCAGUGACAAGGAAGUCAGAGGGAGGGCUGGUUUGCCUCAACCCUCGCCCUGGAUGUGGCAAAAGAUACCACACCGAAGGAAGCUGUAGGGGAUCUGGGACUUAGUCAGGCUAGCUAAGGGCACUGAGUGAUUACAGGGCAAGGCCACAGAGCGGCAGGAAGUUGUAAGUGCAGGGGCCAGGCACAGUCUGAGUGGAGAGCCAUGAUGGCACUCAUCCCUGGCUGGCUCCUGGGCCCAGGCCCUUGCUCAGAAUACAGUGCCCAGGCCCGCCUGGGCAUUGCCUUAAUUCCUGUCUGAGGCUGCCUUCCGUCAUCCUCCUCAAGCUGACUGCUAUCAGCAGGAGAAGGGAAUGCAGAACCACCCCCACCCCAACUCCAGUGUCUCCAGAACUGAGCAGGGACCCUCCCCAUGACGGAGACAGACAACCCAAUGGCAGGGCCUGGGGGAGUUCUAACCUCCCGUGCCCAAGCCUGACUUCCCUUCCCUCUCCAGAUACUGAGGAAAGUGGGUUGGAGGUGGGCCAUGAGGGUGGGGGACAGGGGGAGGGAGAGCCAUUUCCUAAGAAGAGCCCAGGUUGUCUCAGCCCAGGGAGACUGGUUUCAGGAGCUGUUCCUUCAGAAAGGACGAUGGAAAUGGAAGUCACAGCAGGGCUGGGGAACUGGGGACUGGUUAGGUUGGACCCAUGGGUGCAGCACCCUCCAAACUGGUGUCAGAGCCUGCAGAUGAGUCCCGGGAGGAGCGGCCCUGCAGGAAGCGGAUGAUCUUCUCAAUGGUGGCCUCCUGGUAUUCGUGGGACCACCUGUGGGCACAGGAGCCAAUGUGGUUCAGACAGCUGGGCAGAGGGAGCUGCUAGUCAGCUGUUUGCCCACACUCUGCCUGUCAUGGUGAUUUGUACCCUACCCCCCUGGUCCCAGGGCCCUGGGGCUCACUUGAUACCGUUGAAAGUAAGCACAGCCUGCAUGUCCUCAGGCAGGACCUGGGGCUCAGGCCACUCGAAGCCAUCAAUGAUGGGCACAAUGUUCUUGCCGCAGCUUAAAGCAGUCACAAUCUCCUGGAGAAAGAAAGGAAAGGAGGAAGAUACCCCUGUACCCAUCUAGGGACCCUUGUAGCCAGGCAGGUGCUGGGAGGCCCACUGGCCCGAGGCUGGGCCCAGGGCAGGACACCAGUCCUGAUGUCCACCUUGAUGUCUACCUUAACCCUUGUAGUGUAAUAAAAAAUAAAUAUUUUUCCUUUGCCCAGAGUUCCUGGCACAGAGCUGCUAAAACCCUUGGAAUCUCUUGAGUGAUGAGUGUCUUUGUAUGCUAAAGAGAUGAUUCCCCACUGGGGGCCCGGGGGGUGCUAUGGGGGUAGCCUAGAUAGUUUCAGGAAGAGGGCUGGUCACCAGGGAGACCAGGGCAUGACUAGAGGAUUGGAACUUUCAGCCCCACCUCCCAGCCUCCAGAGAGGUGCUGGAGAUUGAGUUCAAUCACCAAUGGCCAAUGAUUUAAUCAAUCAUGCCUACAUAAUGGAACCUCCAUAAAAACCCCCAAACAAGGGGUUUUGAAGAGCCUCCAGGUUGAUAAACAGGUGUAGGUGCUGGGAAGGUGGUAGAAGGCAUGGCAUCCACACCUCCACCCUCCAUACGUAGAGAUCCUAUGUAUCUCUUCCAUUUGGCUAUUCUUGAGCUGUGUCCUUUAUAACUGUGAAAUUAAAUAAUUCAGCUGGGCAUGGUGGGUCACGCCUGUAAUCCCAACACUUUGGGAGGCUGAGGCAGGAGGAUCACUUGAGCCCAGGAUUUUGAGAUUAAUAAUAUUAUUUAUUACUAUUAUUCAAGCUUUGUUAAAUCAAACCUAAAGCUCUUGGAACUUUAAGUUAUUCUGAGCCUUGACAGGAAUUGGUCUCUGCAGCCUGAGUCAUGGGGCAUGCAGCUGCAACUUCCACCUAUUUUUUUUUUUUCUGUAAUUACUUAGGAAGACCAAAUGGCACCAGAGAUAAGACUCCCUUAGAUCCCCACUUAGAUCACCACCCUUUCUCAGGGGGUAAUAAAGUCAUCUUCCUUGGAAUGUAGCAAUCUAUAACCAAUCAAAGCACUGUAACAUACGCACUGGUCUUGUAUGGAAAAUGUUGUAAUCCUGCUAAAAUUCCUCUCUCUUUGCCUGUGGAAGUGAAACCUUAACUUCUCCAGUUUGGAAUGCUCACCCCAUGCCUUUGGAGUCAAUGCUUACUGGGUGGCUAUUCUCAAACUUUGCACUCAAAGAAACUCUAUACUUAGUCUUAUUUUCUGAAUCUCAUUAUUUAAGGUUGACAUAAUAAACAACUAAUAGUAAGUAAAGUG